GUGAGGACCCUUGACCUCUGGCCCAAGAUGGUGGCGCCCAGAGCUUCGCUCUUGCUGCUCCCCUGAGGUGAACUGAAGCCAGCAGCCCCGCAUCAUGUCAAAGCUCGGCCGGGCCGCCCGGGGCCUCAGGAAGCCCGAGGUCGGCGGUGUGAUCCGGGCGAUCGUGCGGGCAGGCCUGGCCAUGCCCGGGCCCCCACUAGGCCCAGUGCUGGGUCAGAGAGGCGUUUCCAUCAACCAGUUUUGCAAGGAGUUCAAUGAGAGGACAAAGGACAUCAAGGAAGGCAUUCCUCUGCCUACCAAGAUUUUAGUGAAGCCUGACAGGACAUUUGAAAUUAAGAUUGGACAGCCCACUGUUUCCUACUUCCUGAAGGCAGCAGCUGGGAUUGAAAAGGGGGCCCGGCAAACAGGGAAAGAGGUGGCAGGCCUGGUGACCUUGAAGCAUGUGUAUGAGAUUGCCCGCAUCAAAGCUCAGGAUGAGGCAUUUGCCCUGCAGGAUGUACCCCUGUCGUCUGUUGUCCGCUCCAUCAUCGGGUCUGCCCGUUCUCUGGGCAUUCGCGUGGUGAAGGAACGUUGUUCUGCAAAUGUUCUAAGAAAUGGAAAGAUCUCCAUGAAGGAUCCAAGUGGGAGAAGUUCAGUGUGACCUGGGUCUGUCGUCCUAGAGCCUCAGUUCAGAAGAGCUUGCAGCUUUCCAGAAGGAACGAGCCAUCUUCCUGGCUGCUCAGAAGGAGGCAGAUUUGGCUGCCCAAGAAGAAGCUGCCAAGAAGUGACCCUUGCCCCACCAACUCCCAGAUUUCAAAGGAGGUAGUUGCAAAAGCUGUGCCCAAGGGGAGGAAGGAGGUCACACCAAUAUGAUGAUGGUUUUCAUGACUUUGAAUGAUAUAUUUUUGUACAUCUAGCUGUAUCGAGGCAUCAGGCCUGAAUAAACAUCCUUUCUUACCCACUGUCAUCUUCUAUCUUGGGACCUCAGGGAAGGGAACCAGUACUGGUGGUAGCCAAUAUGGGCAGACAUUAGGAAAUUGGGGUCUUCAUACUGCUUCUCAGAUGUGCAAACUGAGGUUCAGCCAAGCAAAGUAACUUGCCCAGGUCCUUUUUUUUCUUUUUUAAGUUAUAAUUUUGUUUUAUUGCCCAGGUUCUGAAUUGGUGCCAGAGGUAGGAAUAGAACCCAGGCCUUCUCAUUUGAAAUCCUGUGUUCUUCCCCUCCCCAGGGUGGGAACUAUGGUUGCUAGGGCUGAGGUGUAUUGCUUACUUCUUCCAUCAAAAAUCUCUUUUAUCUCUGAACAACUUGCCACCUCUGCAGAAACAAGUCCCUGUGGAGAUCUCAGUUCAGCCCCAGGCAGGGUUACUACAUGGAGUACCCAGAUCCCAGGGGCUACUUCAGGCCCUUCUACUAAGCUCCUGACCCUGGCUCUGGGUCAGAUGUUGGCUGAACAUGAACUAUUGUAGGGCUGACAGCUACAGACCACAGAAAGAGCAAAGCUUCAGUAGGUUCCUGCCUGAUGGAGAAGUCCUCGGGAAGCCCUUGGCCUUCUAUUUCCUCAUUGUCCUUUCAGAGAAGAGAGCAGGAGUUGGGGGAGAAAGGAGAUUCGCAUUUACUGACCAUCUGUUAUGUGCUAGACACUUCAUUUUACACUGAGAAAAUAUGGAAAGCAUAGAUAAACACCUAAAAGAAAAUAAAAACCUCAUGUUAUCCCACCACCCA